AGCAGAGCGCGGAGCCGGGAGCGCGGGGAGCGCGGGCCGGCGGCGGCGAGGGAGGACGGGGGCGCAGACGGCCGGCGCGCGGCGCGGCUACCAUGGGCGUGCGGUGAGCAGCCGCUCGGGACGACUUCCUCGGCUGCGCGGCGCUCGCGCGGAGCUCCCCGGCCGGCGGUGCGUCCCCACGGUCACCAUGAAAGACGACUUCGCAGAGGAGGAGGAGGUGCAAUCCUUCGGUUACAAGCGGUUUGGUAUUCAGGAAGGAACACAAUGUACCAAAUGUAAAAAUAACUGGGCACUGAAGUUUUCUAUCAUAUUAUUAUACAUUUUGUGUGCCUUGCUAACAAUCACAGUAGCCAUUUUGGGAUAUAAAGUUGUAGAGAAAAUGGACAAUGUCACAGGUGGCAUGGAAACAUCUCGCCAAACCUAUGAUGACAAGCUCACAGCAGUGGAAAGUGACCUGAAAAAAUUAGGUGACCAAACUGGGAAGAAAGCUAUCAGCACCAACUCAGAACUCUCCACCUUCAGAUCAGACAUUCUAGAUCUCCGUCAGCAACUUCGUGAGAUUACAGAAAAAACCAGCAAGAACAAGGAUACGCUGGAGAAGUUACAGGCGAGCGGGGAUGCUCUGGUGGACAGGCAGAGUCAAUUGAAAGAAACUUUGGAGAAUAACUCUUUCCUCAUCACCACUGUAAACAAAACCCUCCAGGCGUAUAAUGGCUAUGUCACGAAUCUGCAGCAAGAUACCAGCGUGCUCCAGGGCAAUCUGCAGAACCAAAUGUAUUCUCAUAAUGUGGUCAUCAUGAACCUCAACAACCUGAACCUGACCCAGGUGCAGCAGAGGAACCUCAUCACGAAUCUGCAGCGGUCUGUGGAUGACACAAGCCAGGCUAUCCAGCGAAUCAAGAACGACUUUCAAAAUCUGCAGCAGGUUUUUCUUCAAGCCAAGAAGGACACGGAUUGGCUGAAGGAGAAAGUGCAGAGCUUGCAGACGCUGGCUGCCAACAACUCUGCGUUGGCCAAAGCCAACAACGACACCCUGGAGGAUAUGAACAGCCAGCUCAACUCAUUCACAGGUCAGAUGGAGAACAUCACCACUAUCUCUCAAGCCAACGAGCAGAACCUGAAAGACCUGCAGGACUUACACAAAGAUGCAGAGAAUAGAACAGCCAUCAAGUUCAACCAACUGGAGGAACGCUUCCAGCUCUUUGAGACGGAUAUUGUGAACAUCAUUAGCAAUAUCAGUUACACAGCCCACCACCUGCGGACGCUGACCAGCAAUCUAAAUGAAGUCAGGACCACUUGCACAGAUACCCUUACCAAACACACAGAUGAUCUGACCUCCUUGAAUAAUACCCUGGCCAACAUCCGUUUGGAUUCUGUUUCUCUCAGGAUGCAACAAGAUUUGAUGAGGUCGAGGUUAGACACUGAAGUAGCCAACUUAUCAGUGAUUAUGGAAGAAAUGAAGCUAGUAGACUCCAAGCAUGGUCAGCUCAUCAAGAAUUUUACAAUACUACAAGGUCCACCGGGCCCCAGGGGUCCAAGAGGUGACAGAGGAUCCCAGGGACCCCCUGGCCCAACUGGCAACAAGGGACAGAAAGGAGAGAAGGGGGAGCCUGGACCACCUGGCCCUGCGGGUGAGAGAGGCCCAAUUGGACCAGCUGGUCCCCCCGGAGAGCGUGGCGGCAAAGGAUCUAAAGGCUCCCAGGGCCCCAAAGGCUCCCGUGGUUCCCCUGGGAAGCCCGGCCCUCAGGGCUCCAGUGGGGACCCAGGCCCCCCGGGCCCACCAGGCAAAGAGGGACUCCCCGGCCCUCAGGGCCCUCCUGGCUUCCAGGGACUUCAGGGCACCGUUGGGGAGCCUGGGGUGCCUGGACCUCGGGGACUGCCAGGCUUGCCUGGGGUACCAGGCAUGCCAGGCCCCAAGGGCCCCCCCGGCCCUCCUGGCCCAUCAGGAGCGGUGGUGCCCCUGGCCCUGCAGAAUGAGCCAACCCCAGCACCGGAGGACAAUGGCUGCCCGCCUCACUGGAAGAACUUCACAGACAAAUGCUACUAUUUUUCAGUUGAGAAAGAAAUUUUUGAGGAUGCAAAGCUUUUCUGUGAAGACAAGUCUUCACAUCUUGUUUUCAUAAACACUAGAGAGGAACAGCAAUGGAUAAAAAAACAGAUGGUAGGGAGAGAGAGCCACUGGAUCGGCCUCACAGACUCAGAGCGUGAAAAUGAAUGGAAGUGGCUGGAUGGGACAUCUCCAGACUACAAAAAUUGGAAAGCUGGACAGCCGGAUAACUGGGGUCAUGGCCAUGGGCCAGGAGAAGACUGUGCUGGGUUGAUUUAUGCUGGGCAGUGGAACGAUUUCCAAUGUGAAGACGUCAAUAACUUCAUUUGCGAAAAAGACAGGGAGACAGUACUGUCAUCUGCAUUAUAACGGACUGUGAUGGGAUCACAUGAGCAAAUUUUCAGCUCUCAAAGGCAAAGGACACUCCUUUCUAAUUGCAUCACCUUCUCAUCAGAUUGAAAAAAAAAAAGCACUGAAAACCAAUUACUGAAAAAAAAUUGACAGCUAGUGUUUUUUACCAUCCGUCAUUACCCAAAGACUUGGGAACUAAAAUGUUCCCCAGGGUGAUAUGCUGAUUUUCAUUGUGCACAUGGACUGAAUCACAUAGAUUCUCCUCCGUCAGUAACCGUGCGAUUAUACAAAUUAUGUCUUCCAAAGUAUGGAACACUCCAAUCAGAAAAAGGUUAUCAUUGGUCGUUGAGUUAUGGGAAGAACUUAAGCAUAUACUGUGUAAACAGUGCCAUACAUUUCUAAAAUCCCAAGUGUAGGAAAAAUAUGCAGACAUACAGAUAUAUAGGCCAACUAUUAGUAAUAAUAUGAAAUAUACUUAAAGAGCUUUUAAAACUUUGUAUUUUUGUACAAAAUAUUUGUCUUUUACAAUUUUUUUCCUUUUUUUUUUUUUGUCAUUUUACCGACAUAAUACAUGGAGCCAAAGAAAACAAUAAUGGUACUAAUAAAAACUCCUAGGGUUUCCUGUCAGAUUUAAUUCUACCCAGUGGCAAAGAAUUUUUUCAAUUGUGGCUUUAAAAAAAUAAUUAAAUAUACAUGUGUAUAUAUAUAUAUAUAUAUAUAUUUUUUUUUUUUUUUUUUUUUAAUGUUUCAUUUCCUCAGAGGAACCAAUCACUUGGAAUGUCUAGAAAUAUCCUUGCAGAUUUUGCCAGUGUCAAUCAAGCCUGCACACAUGCACAGUGAAGCGGGCUGUGCCUGCCUUGAGCCCAUCACCAGCCAACAUUCUUGACGUGUGCCUGACCAGACACAGAAGAAAUGGGCAACUCAAGACGUGCUUCCACUUCAUUUUGGUGGAGUCGGGAGGUGUGGGGGAUGGAGAGGCAUCUGUUGGGAAGGGCACUGAAUCUGGCCUAUCUGGAAGGCCCUGUGUCAUGGCUGAGCUAUGACUGUACUUGGCAUCAGAUCCCUACAGAGCCAACAUUAACUGUCAGGAACGUAUGGCGUCACAUCAGCCAAAGGCAGAGAUGCUAGAAAGAUGGGAACCGGCUACGUGUUACCUGGAAAGUUUGUUUUCUUAAGUCAUAUUCCAAAAACAUAACUCCAAGGCAUACGCAUGAUAAAAUGCAAGAAUAAACUUUUGGCCACUUUGUGGAACUCUUAAAAGAACCUUUCCAGCCGGGCGCAGUGGCUCAUGCCUGUAAUCCCAGCACUUUGGGAGGCCGAGGCAGGCAGAUGACUUGAGGUCAGGAGUUCGAGACCAGCCUGGCCAACGUGGCAAAACCCCAUCUCUACUAAAAAUAAGAAAAUUAGCCGGGUGUAGUGGCACAUGCCUGUAAUCCCAGCUACUCAGGAGGCUGAGGCAGGAGAAUCGCUUGAGCCCAGGAGGCAGAGAUUGCAGUGAGCCAAGAUCGCACCACUGCACUCCAGCCUCGGUGACAGAGCAAGACUCCAUCUCAAAAAAAAAAAAAAAAAAAAAACCUUUCCUCUGAGCCCAUCUUCCUUUCGCUCCUUGACUUUCCUUGACUUGCUGUUGGAAAGUCUAAUAUGAAAAGGGCUGAAACUAGGCAUUAAAUAUAACUGAUGCUCAAAGGUAAGAUUUCCAUCCAACAGAUUCCUUCUCCCUCCCAAGGGUCUUCCCAGGCAGUGCUGCUACUUAUCCCAAAUAAAAUGGUAAAAGAAUAAAGACAGCCGGGCGCGGUGGCUCACGCCUGUAAUCCCAGCACUUUGGGAGGCCGAGGCGGACGGAUCACAAGGUCAGGAGAUCGAGACCAUCCUGGCUAACACGGUGAAACCCCGUCUCUACUAAAAAUACAAAAAAAAAAUUAGCCGGGCGCGGUGGCGGGCGCCUGUAGUCCCAGCUACUCGGGAGGCUGAGGCAGGAGAAUGGCGUGAACCCAGGAAGCGGAGCUUGCAGUGAGCCGAGAUCGCGCCACUGCACUCCAGCCUGGGCGACAGAGCGAGACUCAUCUCAAAAAGAAAAAAAAAAAAGAAUAAAGACAGAGUUUGACUUUCCCACCUGCGAACAAGUGGACUGUACUGCUUUGCCCACAGUCUCCAUUCCCCAUUCAUGCUGUUUUCACAGCCCAGUAAUGGCCAACUGCUCAGCACCUGUGUGCCCUGCUGUCAGGCAGGUGGGACCCACAGUCCUCUGGGCCUAAACUGCUGAAGCCUGCACCACAAGGCGGGCACGGCAUUCCAACACCUCUUCAGGCUCAACAGCCUUUAGAGGCUACACUGAGUCCUCUUUUUCAUGCUCUUCCUGGUUUUCAAGUGUCAAUUAAAAUUUGUCUUCAGAAGAAACUUGAAAAUAAGUAUCUGAUGCCGUCAUCAGGAUAGACUAGUAUUAGCUUUCGCAGCUGAAGUUAUUGCUCUCCCAGCCCUAAUAAUAACUUACCAAGUGCUUAUUAUUUAUCAGGCACUGGUCCAAGUCCUUCAAUCAGAUUGUCUCACCUGAUCCUCCCAACAGCCCUAGGAAGCAGGUCUUACUACACUCCCCAUUUCACAGGGACUGGGGCUUGGGGAGGUGAUGCGGUUUCCUGGGUCACUCCAUUACUGAGUAGUGAGACAGGAUUCAGACGCAAGCUUUGAAAAUGUUCUAAUUUUCUUUAGAAGGAAGGGCCCUUCUUAAUAGCACACUGAAUAAAAUCAAAUGAAUAAUCACACAUUACAAGAUGCCUCCUAUACGUCUCUAUAUUUAGCUACUUACAUACCAGGUUUCUUUUUUGUUUGUUUUUGUUUUUAAGACAGAGUCUCGCUCUGUCACCCAGGCUGGAGUGCGGUGGCGCGAUCUCGGCUCACUGCAAUCUCUGCCUCCCAGGUUCAAGCGACUCUCCCGCCUCAGCCUCUGCAGUAGCUUAGGGACUACAGGUGCGUGCCACCAUGCCAGGCUAAUUUUUGUGUUUUUAGUAGAGACACGGUUUCGCCAUUUUGGCCAGGCUGGUCUCAAACUCCUGACCUCAGGUGAUCCACCCGCCUUGGCCUCCCAAAGUGCUGGGAUUACAGGUGUGAGCCACCGUGCCCGGCCUACACACCAGCUUUCUAUUCACCUACACACAACUGAUGCUCUUUUGGAGUGGAGAGUUUUAGUAAAAUAUGAUGGGGUCUUCAGGCACCUGAGUUGCUACUUACUACUAUGAGAAGAUAGAAAAUGUUUUUUCCUCUAAACAGCUUUUGAAAGAAUGAAUGCACAACAAGGCAAAAAAUAAAAACUUUCUUUUCCUUUUCUACGA